CUUCAUUCUGCAGUUGGUGCCAGAACUCUGGAUCCUGAACUGGAAGAAAAUGUCUAUCCAGGUUGAGCAUCCUGCUGGUGGUUACAAGAAACUGUUUGAAACUGUGGAGGAACUGUCCUCGCCGCUCACAGCUCAUGUAACAGGCAGGAUCCCCCUCUGGCUCACCGGCAGUCUCCUUCGAUGUGGGCCAGGACUCUUUGAAGUUGGAUCUGAGCCAUUUUACCACCUGUUUGAUGGGCAAGCCCUCCUGCACAAGUUUGACUUUAAAGAAGGACAUGUCACAUACCACAGAAGGUUCAUCCGCACUGAUGCUUACGUACGGGCAAUGACUGAGAAAAGGAUCGUCAUAACAGAAUUUGGCACCUGUGCUUUCCCAGAUCCCUGCAAGAAUAUAUUUUCCAGGUUUUUUUCUUACUUUCGAGGAGUAGAGGUUACUGACAAUGCCCUUGUUAAUGUCUACCCAGUGGGGGAAGAUUACUACGCUUGCACAGAGACCAACUUUAUUACAAAGAUUAAUCCAGAGACCUUGGAGACAAUUAAGCAGGUGGGACACAGUGCUAGGUGAUGUUCAGGAAUUUAGAAUUUGGAACUUAAAAUUAAUUCAACAUAAAUUAUUCAUGCUGCGAAUGUAUGAUUCUAACUUGAUGAGGACACACAGAAUGACCAUUCCAAGCUCCAAAUGGACUGCACUGAUUGCCUCUGUCUAUGAUGCUUUCCUGCAAUUGGUGUAAUUUGGUGAAAAGAACAUGAGAGCCACAUUAAGUUUCAAAUCCUAGCAUUGUCAACAAUGACUAGCUAUUUGACAUAGGACAAACAUUGUUUCUUCAUCUCUAAAAUUUUAAACACUUACAUGGAUUGGAGAGAACCCAUAUAAAAUGCCUAACAUAUUCAUUCAUUCAUUCAUGACACAAAUACUUAUCAAGUGCUUUCCAUAUUCAGAAUUUAUGCUAGAUGCAAGGGAUAGAUCAAUGAGUAGGGUAACAUGGUCCCUGCCUUUCAUAGCUUUUAUAAGCUAGCAUGAACCUGGUAAAUACUGGGUGCUCAAAAAAUUAUAGCUACUGAUACUGAAAAUCAUGCUAUUUAUGGUUCUAGGCAAGUAUGUUGCACUAAUUUGCCCCUUCUUAUAGAUACUUCUUAUUAGAAAUAAAGCUAUAUCUUGAAUGAAAUAGCAUAGAACAAAAUUUCAGCAAUAUUUGGAAGUGACAAAUUUUAUGGAGAACUUAGGGAAUCUCAAUGCAGCAGUCCUUAGAUACACAUUUUGAACCAAUAUUUACUAAGAUACACCUAUUUACAAGGCAUUGUUCUUGUCUUCAGGUGACUUAAUGUCUAGGUGGAGAAAUCAAAUAUGUAACUGUAAUAGGACAAAGAAUAUGACGAGUCUUUUAAGAAGGAAAAUCUUUUAAGAAAGCAUAAAUACGAAAGGAAUUACUUCUGGAAGUAGUUGGCAAUGCAAGGUGGGACAGGUGAAAGAAGGCUUAAAGGGAAAGGCUUUGGGCUGGAAGUUAAAAGAGAGGGAUGAUUUCAGUGAAUUUAGAGAAAGGAUAUGCUAGAUGGAGGGGGUAAAGCGAUCAAAAGCAUGGAGGUAGAAGGUGUUCAUGAAAACUGGAGAAUAAUCUCCUUGGACUAGACUUGCAGCAUUUCUCAGUGGAGGUAUUAGUAUGACAUUAGGCAGGGGGUGACUCAUCAUCAUGGAGACGUCCCACACAUGGGAGAGGUUUGGCAUCCCUGGCCUCAUCCACUAAACACCAGUCAUGUUUUCAAUCAUUAUACAAACCCAAAACGCUCCUGACAUUUCCGUAUCUUCCCCUAGGGGGCAAUAACACUCCCAGUUGAGAACUAGUUGCCUAGAGUAGUUAAUGUCAAGGGGAAUAUUGAGACACAGGGUAGGAUGAAAUUAAAAGCUUGAAUAAUUGGCUAUACAUUUGGAAUAUGUUGUUUAGCUAAUGGGAAGCUACUGAAAGUUUUUGCUCAAAGAAGUAGUAUGAGUAGGGCUAUAUUUUCAGAUGUUUAUUUGGGGAGCCAUGUGUGGGCUGUACGGGAAGGCAAAAGAGAUACAGUAUAGCUGGGAGACCAAGAGGUGAAACUAAAAGCCAGAACCACAAAUGCAGUACUGGUAAAAAUAAGAAGAAAAAAAAUAGUCUCAACAUUGAGUCUCAAUAGCACAAGCUGAUCUAUAAUUCUCAACAGACUAUUUACUAUGUCUUAACAUACACUCCCCAUAGCUCUUUCUUGUUUAUGUUGUGUGUGUGUAACCAUAUACAAGUGUGUGUGUAGCUCCUUUAGAGAAGAACAAAAGCUGAGUUUCUAAAUCAUUCAUUUGACUUUGAUAGGGAAUCUGUAUUACAAUUACAUGAUAUUUUAAUUAGAAAUAUAGAAGCUAUGGUAUGGCUGCAGAAUAGACUUUAUUAGGAGUCAGGUUCCACUGUUACUAGCACUGUAAAAUGUAAUUUUAAAAAUGUGAAAUUUUUGAUUGUUUACUGUUAUUAACCAGUGCCUUUGCCUCCAGCCUGAUUCCCUUAAAUACAAUUUAUUUAAGGCAGCAGUAGCAAUUUUUUAAAAUAUAAAUAUGAAAGUAUUACUCCACCUAGGGAAUCCAUAACUUCCCAAAUAAAGUCCAAGCGAAGGUC